AGCGCUGGACGCGGCUAGAGCUGGGGCUGCCGCGCCCUCCACCUCCUUCUCCAAAGGCCUCCCCGGACCCCUGGCUCGGGCCCAGCCUGCGACUCCGCCAUGCCCUGGAGGAGGCGCAGGAACCGGGUGAGUGCCCUGGAGGGCGGCCGGGAGGAAGAGGCGCCCCCGGAGGCUGCCGCUGUGCCUCCGGCGCUGUUAACGUCCCCGCAGCAGACGGAGGCGGCGGCCGAGCGGAUUCUGCUCCGGGGCAUCUUCGAGAUCGGGAGGGACAGUUGUGACGUGGUGCUGAGCGAGCGAGCACUGCGGUGGCGGCCCAUUCAGCCCGAGCGCCCGGCGGGUGAUUCUAAGUAUGACUUGCUAUGUAAAGAAGAAUUUAUUGAACUCAAAGACAUAUUCUCUGUGAAACUGAAACGGCGUUGUUCUGUUAAACAGCAGAGAAGUGGUACUUUAUUAGGUAUCACACUCUUCAUCUGCUUGAAAAAGGAACAAAAUAAACUAAAGAAUUCUACACUUGAUCUUAUUAAUUUAAGUGAAGACCACUGUGACAUAUGGUUUAGACAGUUCAAGAAAAUAUUGGCAGGCUUUCCAAACAGACCGAAGUCAUUAAAAAUACUCCUUAACCCCCAAAGUCACAAAAAAGAAGCUACCCAGGUUUAUUAUGAGAAGGUUGAACCUCUGUUGAAGCUUGCAGGAAUAAAAACUGAUGUAACAAUAAUGGAAUAUGAAGGGCACGCUCUGUCACUGCUUAAGGAAUGUGAACUCCAGGGAUUUGAUGGUGGGCAUCGGAAACCAUUGUUCGCAAUACAUUGGAGUGUACAGAGAUUGUUCACUGGCAUGCAAACGUUAGAACCAAGUGUUGUCUGUGUUGGUGGAGAUGGAUCUGCUAGCGAAGUAGCCCAUGCUUUGCUUCUGAGAGCUCAGAAGAAUGCUGGGAUGGAAACAGACCGAAUCCUGACUCCUGUCAGAGCACAGCUUCCACUUGGCUUAAUACCAGCAGGAUCUACCAAUGUAUUGGCACAUUCUCUUCAUGGAGUUCCUCAUGUGAUAACUGCAACAUUGCACAUUAUAAUGGGGCAUGUACAGCUGGUCGACGUCUGCACCUUCAGCACCGCUGGCAAGCUUCUUCGCUUUGGGUUCUCAGCCAUGUUUGGCUUUGGUGGAAGAACUUUGGCUCUGGCAGAAAAAUAUCGAUGGAUGUCCCCUAACCAACGGAGAGAUUUUGCUGUUGUUAAGGCACUGGCAAAACUUAAGGCAGAAGACUGUGAAAUAUCAUUUUUACCAUUUAACAGCUCUGAUGAUGUGCAAGAAAGGAGGGCACAGGGAUCUCCCAAAUCUGACUGUAAUGAUCAAUGGCAAAUGAUCCAGGGUCAGUUCUUGAAUGUCAGCAUUAUGGCAAUUCCUUGCCUGUGUUCAGUGGCACCUAGAGGCUUGGCACCUAAUACCAGAUUAAAUAAUGGAAGUAUGGCUCUUAUAAUUGCCCGAAACACUUCUCGGCCAGAAUUUAUAAAACACCUGAAAAGAUAUGCCAGUGUAAAAAAUCAGUUCAAUUUUCCAUUUGUUGAGACUUACACUGUUGAGGAAGUAAAAGUUCAUCCAAGGAAUAAUACUGGUGGAUAUAAUCCAGAGGAGGAGGAGGAUGAAACUGCUUCAGAAAAUUGUUUCCCUUGGAAUGUAGAUGGUGACUUAAUGGAAGUUGCAUCAGAGGUCCAUAUUAGAUUGCAUCCAAGACUUAUCAGUCUUUAUGGAGGAAGCAUGGAAGAAAUGAUUCCAAAGUAACAUGUAAUUGUUUCUAAAAGAAAUGUACAAACUAGAAUUUUAAUAUAAAGAAAUGUGGCCAUGCUUUAAACCUGUGGUCCCCACCCUUUUUGGGACCAGUUUCAUGGAAGACAAUUUUUCCGUGGAUGGGGGAAUGGUUUCAGGAUGAACUGUUCCACCUCAGAUCAUCAGGCAUUAGAUUCUCUUGAGGAACAUGGCACUCUAGAUCCCUCACAUACCAGUUCACCAUAUGGUUCGCACUUCUAUGAGAAUCUAAUGCUGCUGCUGAUCUGACAGGGGGAGGAACUCAGUAAUGCUCCAUUGCUCUAACCUCCUGCUGUGUGGCCAAACGGAUAUCCUAAUAGAAAUUGAUGUUACUAACAAUUAGCCUCUAGGGCUUUAAAAGUCAAGAUGAAAUAUCAAUUCAAAUUCUGUUUUUAGAUAUCAAUUCAAAUUCUUUUUUUUACAAUGUGUUUAUUGGACACACAAAAAAACUUUGCAACCAUCAUAAUACAUCAAUAUUUAACCUAGAUAAUUCUGAAAUAAUUUGGAUUCUUUCAUUUUUCAGGAUUUGAGCUCAUCAAUUAUGUUAAAUUUCCUAUAUUCUGUUACAAAUAUAAUACAGAUUUCAUAAGUCUGCCUUGAUUCACUGCUCCCUAAUCCAGAGCAGUUAAAUUUCAAAAUCACAUAGUUAUAUAGCCUACCUGCCAAAAAAGAAUAACCCAUCCCUGUCUUCUUAAAGUGGUAGGGUUUUAAAAUUCAUGAUACAAGUAACAAAGUAAGUUGAUAACAAAUACUAUUUUGAACUGGGCAAAAUCUAGCCCAAUAUGUAAUUGUGUUCCCCUUGUAUCUGAGAGGCCUGUGUUGGACAACCAUAGUACUCUGCUUUCACUGUGCUCAGAUAACCUGAAAUAUAUAGUUGUUUCUGAGUAGUUCUGAGUAGGAAAGAACCAAAUGUAAAUUUCCUUAGAGACCAUCCUGGAGAAGACAGUUCUAAAUCGGGGCUUGAUUUUUCAUCUAUGAUCCUAGAUGUUCUCCUGAAAGAAUGACUAGCCUUUUUAUAACGAUACAAAGUUUUUUAAAAAUACAUAAAUGUCAUAAAGUUUAUUCCUGUGUAUACACACUCUGGGUUCAGGAGGUUUUGUGCUUACAUUUCACUACUCAAAUGCCUUCGCAAAUCUCAGAACAUUCCUCACCAUCACUGCAGGCCUGUGAACAGAUAACUUUCAUCAAUUAGGAUGGCUGGCUAGUGGCAGGGACUUCAUAUAAAGAAAUCUUUCCCAGAAUUGUUUUUCCACAUUGCCUUCUAAUUUGAUCACUCCCUAUAACAGAUGUUCAAAAUUCGGCCACAGCUCUCUUAUGAAGGCAGAGUCAGAUAAAAUGAUAUUCUGCAAUUAUCUAGAUCAUAAGCAUAAAAUAAAUAUUACAAAAAUGAUUGUAUUUAAAGAAAUUUUUUAAAAUCCAGAAAGUCAUUUAAAAUAGAACCUCAUAUAGUAUGAACAAACUAUAAAAAUAUUUUACAUUUCAUGAAAA